UGUGGAGUCAAAAUAAAAUAGACCUUCCUGACUUAAUCUGGAUAUGUGGGAUGAAAGAGAAGGAAAGAACAGAUGUUUUGAACGCCACAUCAUGGAAGAAGGGUAUUAUAAUGGCUAGACAUGUUAGUUGAGAUGGGGACUAGUUUGUGGAGAGGGGAAGAUGAAUUCAAUUUUGUAUGGACUGACUGGAGGUGGUACUGAUAUUAAUACCUCCAGGCGGUAUUUUCCAUAGGGAAUUGAAGACCCAGAACUGGAUUUCAGAAAAUGCUUUAAGUCAUGAGCAUAUAGAAUAUAGAGAACACCAGUCAUUGCUGGGGAUUUACUGUGUGGUAGCCUCUGGGCUAAGCGCUUUACAUGCAGUUCUCAUUUUAUUCUCAUAACUCUGAGGUGGGUCCCAGUUAGCCUCAUUUUACAGAGGAGGAAACAGAAACUCAGAAAGGCUAGGUACCUUGACUAGGAUCGCCCAAGUAGUGUAAAACUGGGAGUAGUUCCAAGCCUGUGCACUUCCUGCUGUAUUUCCCUCUGCUGUUCCAAGGACUGCUAUAUUAAAUGGUAGAUUGAAUGUACCUUAGAUACCACUUUUUUGUCUCUUAAUUUCAGAGGUUGUGUGUGCUGUUUGCUGUUUGUUGUUUUGUUUUGUUUUUUGGGAUGGAGUUUUGCACUGUUGCCUAGGCUGGAGUGCAGCGGCGCAGUCUUGGCUCACUGCAACCCCUACCUCCCGGAUUCAAGGGAUUCUCAUGCCUCAGCCUCCCAAGUAGCUGGGAUUAUAGGCGCCAACCACAACACCUGGCUAAUUUUUGUUUUUGUUUUUGUUUUUUUUUUUUGGUAGAGAGGGGGUUUCACCAUGUUGGCCAGGCUGGUCUCAAAUUCCUGACCUCAGGUGAUCCGCCCGCCUAGGCCUCCCAAAAUGCUGGCAUUACAGGUGUGAGCCACCACGCCUGUUUGUUCUCUCUUUAAAGUCUAUGUGUAGGUUGGUUUUAAAUCAGUGCACCUCAAACUAUAGAGGCCAGGGUACGACAGUUUGGAGCAGAGUCUGAAAGUGGUGGUUAUAAACUUCAGACUCUAAGUAAGGACCAAUGGCUACUGUGCGUAUCCUCCAGGGCCCUUCCAUAUUUUCUUCUAAGAACUAAGUCUGAACAAGUCUGUCAUGACAGCAAGUUUACUACUUGUUACUGUAAUUGUGUUCUUUCCCCAUAAUUCACCAAUUCCUGAAAAUACACUUUUAAAUAAGUAAUGGAUAUUUAUAUGUUUAGUCAGUCUUUGGAGAUUCAUGGCCUUCGAAAGGGUUAAUAUAAUUGAUGCUUGUGUUAUUAAUAUUGAGUGCCAACAAGGCUCUGGAGAGCAGUAAGAGAGGAAAGGGUGAAGAAAAUGGCCUCAAUAAAGUUGACUCUGGAGCACAAAUGAUUAGUGUGCACAUUAAGAUCAAAUUACGAAGGCAGAGAUUCCUACCAUCAGAGCAAGAGCUGGAAUUUUUAAAAUAAUAAACUUCAUUUUAAAAACUCAGCAUAUUUAAGAGAGUUUUAUUCCUUGCUUGCUAAGCCUCAAAGUUUUUCCAAAUCUAUUUUGCAUGUGGUUUUGUAUUUUCAUGACAAUUCUGAAACCACAGGUGUUGGAAGACAAUUCUAAAGAUACCAAGUUUUAAGUAUAUUUUGACAUAUUUUGAAACUAGCCAUAGUUUUAAUCAAGAAAAACAUUUUUCAGUGUACACUGCUGAUAGAAGCAGAUUUCAGUUAUGAAAGUUUGGAAAUAAUACUUUAAUAAGGCACUUCAUUUUAAAACUGAAAGCAAUUCUAGUUUGCUGCUAGUUUAAAAAGUUUAUAGUUUAAUGUGAUCUGAGAAAGUAAACCAAGACCAAGUGGAAACACUUAUUUAUCUUGAGGUUGCAACAAGCAAAUUGAGCUGGGAGACUUCUGGGUGAGGAAGGAUCUGCUACUUAAAUCAGGCUCUAAGAUAUGAUAGAUGGUGCUCUACAUGCCAUCACUUUGAAAGAUUUAAAUGUUUCUUAUGUAAGAAUAUCUUAAUCAGGAUUUCUCCCAAGUAUGUGCUUCCAAAGCACCAGGGCUACAAGGUGUUCUGCCAAAAAAAGGGUUCUGAGGUCAGAAAAGUUUGAGAGGUUCUUCUUGCUCACUUCAUACCACCCCCUCACUGGCCUCCCAACCCCAUUUGAAAAGUAAUCAUGCAUAUUAACAUAUUUAGGGUCAUUGCCCUGCCUCCCAGGAAACCAGUUUAACUUUGCUUAACUGGCCUUUAUUGGACUUAUCUGUCCUUUAAAAUUUUUUUCACUAUAUCUUGAACUGCUCUCCUACACAGCACACUUUGAGUAACACUGCUUGAAAUACUGCUUCUCAAUUUCAUUCUCCCAAAUGACAACAAAAGUGAUUAUGGUGAAACCAGAAGCAACAAUAAGGUUGUUGGAUCAGGUGACUCUUAACUAAGAAUCACUCAGCUCUGAAACUGACUUUAAGUGCAUCACAAACUUCAUGUUCUUCUUUAAGAUAUUGGCAAAAGUAGAUAAAUUUCAAGUCACUCAAGUAUAUUAUAACUUAAAACCCUUUCACGUGAAUCAUUGUUUCUCAGAUUAGUGAUUUGAGAUCUCCAAGGGAUAUUAGGUAGGGUAAAUGAUUGACAAAAGAAUCCUUCAAGUUUGAAACUUGAUAAUAUGAACUGCUAUGGGGUCAGCUGGGCCAACAGCAAGAAGGGGAGCUAUGAUCUGCACUGGAGGAUUUUCUCCUUUCUUCAAGUCUGCUGCAGCAGAGGGGCAGUUACAGUUAUCACUUAAACUCCAAAUGACCAUUCGGAGAUGGAAUGCUAUCUUUGGUUGGAGAAAGAAUUGAGGAUAGGGAUGAUGGGCCAAGCAAAUAAUAGAUCCUCAAUAAAUGUUUAUUGAAUACAUAUGGAACAGGGAUGGAGUAUUCAGAGACUAAACAUUUAGUUUGUGGUGCUGAUACUUGUCAAGAUUAUGGUUAAAACAAAUACAACUUGCCAAUGGAGAGAAAUGGGAAUGAACCUGAAAAUUAAAACUAGCUGCCGUUCAAACUGUUUAAUUCUGGUGGGCUUUUGAAUUCUACCUUGCUAGCAUGUGUUCCUAGGUUAUAAUGAAGUCUUGGUGUAUACAUUAAUAUUAACCAAUCAGGAAAAAAGGCACAUCAUAAGCUAGAACCCUCUGGGCCUCAUCAAAACCUCAGUAUGACAGGUAAUCAGCACUGGACGAUAGAUUUAUUAUAUAAGAAUGAGGGCCUUCUUUCCCUUCUGCCACACCGCCUUCCCCCAUUUCCCUGCAACACACCUCUUGUUUCUGGCCCACAGAGCAUAAUGAAAGCUCUUCUGGCCCAUUUUCUCAGUGCCUGCCUGGGAGUAGACUGGGUAAAGCUCCAGUCUUAAGUAUUUUGUUCAGAGUGUGACCUGGAAGAUGACAAGCAGCACUGCUUCUGCCCAUUGCAGCAAUGAGGAAACUCAGGACAAAGGGAAGAUGCUGAAAAGUAAAAUAAAAGAACCGAGAAUAUCGGUAGAAUAAAAAGAGAAUCCCAAGCUGGCUGCAUGCUUUGGUUCUGUUCAAUGUUCAUGGGCUGGUGUGCUGUCAGGCUAAGUACUGGGCUCAACAAAGAAUGAGACUUUUCCUUCUGUAAGUGUGCAGUCUGUUAAGGGAGAUGCUACGGAGGGGUGUAGCUUUGUCAGUGUGCCAGAGCCCAGCUGAAUCUGUGUUUCUCUCUCUCUCUUUUUUUUUUUUUUUUUUUUUUGAGAGGGAGUCUCACUUUGUCGCUCAGGCUGGAGUGCAAUGGCACGAUCUCGGCUCACUGCAGCCUCUGCCUCCCAGGUUCAAGUGAUUCUCCUAUCUCAGCCUCCCAAGUAGCUGAGACUACAGGCGCCCGCCACCAUGCCCAGCUAAUUUUAUUUUUUUAUUUUUAGUUGAGACGGGGUUUCACCAUGUUGAUCGGGUGGUCUCGAACUCCUGACCUCAGGUGAUCCGCCUGCGUUGGCUUCCCAAAGUGCUGGGAUUACAGGUGUGAGCCACCACGCCUGGCCCUGUGUUUCUUAUAUAGCUAAAUAUUAGUAUAGUUUACAAGGUGUAAAACACUGAUAAUUCCUUGCUAGAUUUUAAACUAAUUUUCAAAACUAAAAACUAGAAAUACAAAAGUGCCCUAAAGGAACAUAGAUGUUAUUUUUGAAGUUUGGUUUGUGUUUGUGCUUCACUGGUAAGGAUGAAGUUCAGUAAACUUUAGGAUAAAGUUAUUGUGUCUGUAGGCAUGACAGCAUUUUAUUAUACAGAGUGAAAAAAAUACUGUCCUUGAGUAAGAAAAUAACAAAGCUUCAGAUGCCUGUAUGCAAGUCACAAUGGCUUUUGAGGCAGUCCCAUAGAAAAGAUUGUACCUAUAAUAUGGGUAAUAUUUUAAUUUUCAUGUUGAAAUGACCAGCUUUUAAGCUAAUAAAUGAGUUUUCUUCUUUGAUAGAGCAGAUUCUAGAAAUUUUAAAGUAGAACACAUCGAAAGUAUUCUUCUGUCGUUGUUGACUAACCUAUGGUGGCUCUUUUGUUGCUCUUAUGUGUUUAUGACUUAGUCAUGUAUCUCUGCCCUGUUACCCUGCCAGGAAAUCCAUGUGCUCUUGCCAUAGUCCCAAAGUCUCAUACCUAACUGGGCACAGUGACCUGUUUAGUGUUCCAUGGCCAUGGACUAACUACAGGGUCCAGAAUGGAUUCAGGGACACCCAAGUAUUCAAUUUGUUUCCUACCACUACAUCAGACCACCUUUCCAUUUAUCUUCCAGCUUUCUCCCAUUCAGACAUACAUUUUCUGUUUAUGCUCUUUAAGUUUUUAAAUCUCAUUUGGUUCCAAAAAUGUUUUAGGUAAUUUUUAAUAAAAUGUAAAUAUAUUUAAGACUUUUGAAAUGAAAAGCCAAAAGCUGAAAGGAGGUGGAGGUGGGAUAAAAGGAAAAAGAAGCACAAAUGUACCGAGUGCCUGAGCUUCUUCACCUACCAGUGUUUCUAGUCCUAUUUUAGAAUGAUACUGAUUCAAAGGAAAUUGUCACAUGGAAUCCUUUUACAGAAUUACACAACUGUCAGGGGCUUAAGAGGUCUACCAAGGUAGCCAUGAAUUUUAUGUCACAUACUCUACGUGGAUUUUGUUCAGUCUUUGUUUAAACACUUCCAGCAACAGAUAACUUACUGCUUCCUGAGGCAUUUGUUCUACAUUCAGGCAGUUAUUAGAAAUUUCAUUUUGCACUACCGAGCUCUGUGUCCAUGUAACUUCAUUGUUCUGAUUCUGCACCCAUUAGCCAAACAGAAUAAAAAACCGAAAUUGGCCUUUAGUGUGUGCCAAGGUAUGUGUGUGUGUUUUAAAGUUAAACACCUUUAGUUUUUACAACCAUGUCUGAAUGUCAGACUUUCAGAAACUUUACUGUUCUGGGCCACUUCUUUACUUUACUUUUAUGCUUUCAUGAUUAAAUCUAUGUAAUUUUUAUUUUUAUCAGUUACACAUGUGUGUAUUUUUUUUUUUUUUUUGAGAUGGAAUUUCACUCUUGUUGCCCAGACUGGAGUGCAAUGGCGCGAUCUUGGCUCACUCAACGUCCACCUCCCGGGUUCAAGUGAUUCUCCUGCCUCAGCCUCCCUAGUAGCUGGGAUUACAGGCACCCGCCACCAUGCCCAGCUAAUUUUUUGUAUUUUUAGUAGAGACAGGGUUUCACUAUGUUGGCCAGGCUGGUCUUGAACUCCUGACCUCAGGUGAUCCACCCGUCUCAGCCUCCCAAAGUGCUGGGAUUACAGAUGUGAGCCACUGCGCCCAGCUCAUAUGUUUGUAUUUUAAAGAGUUAAGCAUUUCUAGGGCUUGUUAUUUUAAAAAGCUCCCCACCCUCCCCAUUUUCUGCUGCCCUGAGACCACCACUUUUAAAUCUUUAAUUCUUUUGCUUUUCCCCCUAUAUAUCUUUAAUAUGCUUAUACUGCUACCUCCUCGCUUUUCAAUUUUUGACAUUAAUUUUGGACUCCACUGUAGAAGAUAAAGAUUGAGCUGUCUUCCAACACCAUCCUUUGCCCUACCCUGUGCACCUACUUCGGGUUGCCCUUAUCCUUCUGCUGCAGAUAUAUCAUCAUAACUUUGUUUGGAUCAAUGUUCAGUCUUUUUUGUUUGUUUGUUUGAGAUGGAGUCUACUCUGUCACCCAGGCUGGAGUGCAGUGGUGUGAUCAUAGCUCACUGCAGCCUCAACCUCCCAGGCUCAAGUGAUCCUCCCACCUCAGCCUCCUGAAUAGCGGGGACCACAGAUUUGCACCACCACGCCUAGCUGAUUUUUAAAAAUUAUUUUGUAGAGAUGAGUUCUCAUUAUGUUUCCCAGGAGGGUCUCAAACUCUGGGGCUCAAGUGAUCCUCCUGCUUUGGCCUCCUGAAGUGCAGGGAUUACAGGCGUGAGCCCUCGCACCCUGCCUAAUGUUUAGUCUUCAUCUUAUGACUAAGUGGUUGCUCUUAACAGCCGAGUCAUGUAGUAUUUCAUCAUUUGUCACUCUUGGAGAUCGUGGUUGUCUUGUUCUACUGUCUACCCAGCUUUCUAUUAAUAUGCACUUAUAACUAAUUGGCUUAUAAACUCUCACCUAGUUGUGUGACUCUCCUUUGAGUAAGCUCAGAUACCUUAGAUAUUCUUUCAGUUUCAAUUUCCUGAAUAGAUCUCUCCCAUACCUCCAAACUGGGCUGGAUACUCUUCAGGCCUGCUUUUUUACAAAGCUGUCAAUUUAAGAUCUCCCUUCACAUCAUACCUGGAAUUUUUUUUUUUUUUUUGAGAUGGAGUUUUACUCUUGUUGCCCAGGCUAGAGUGCAAAGGUGCGAUCUCGGCUCACCACAACCUCUACCUCCUGGGUUCAAGUGAUUCUCCUGCCUCAGCCUCCCGAGUAGCUGGGAUUACAGGCAUGCGCCACCACGCCUGGCUAAUUUUGUAUUUUUAGUAGAGACGGGGUUUCUCCAUGUUGGUCAGGCUGGUCUCGAACUCCUGACCUCAGACAAUCUGCCCACCUUGGCCUUCCAAAGUGCUGGGAUUACAGGUGUGAGCCACCGUGCCAGGCCCAUUCUUUCUUGUAUUGGAUUCCCAAUUAUCUGGAUCCCAUGUGCUUUUUUAGUUUAUUUUUUAAUUUACAUACGGUACAAUUCACUUUUUGUUCUACAGUUGUAUGAACUUUGACAGACGCAUGGCCUUAUGGAGCCACCACCACCAGUAGCAAGAUACAGAACAGUUCUCACUUCCAAAAAUUCCCUUGAGCUGCCCCUUUGUCAUCAGAUCACUCCUCUACCCUUGGCAACCACUGAUCUAUUCCUGUAGUUUUGCUUUUUCCAGAAUGUCAUAUAAAUGGAAUCAUACAGUAUUGUAAACCUUUUGAGUUUGGCUUCUUUUCUUCAGUGUAAUGCAUUUGAGAUGCAUCCAUGCUAUUGCAUGCAUCAAUAGUUUGUUUUUAUGGCUAAGUAGUAUUCCAUUAUAUGAAUAUAUCAUAGUUUAUUCACCAGUUGAAGAACACGGGGUUGUUUCCAGUUUGGGAUGAUUAUUAAUAAAGCUCCUGUGAACACUUCUAUGCAGUGUGAAUGUUUUCAUUUAUCUUUGGUAACUAUCUGGGAGUGGAAUUGCUGGGUUGUAUGGUAAGUGAAUGUUUAUAAGAAUCUGCCAAACUGUUUUCCAAAUGGGCUGUACCAUUGUGCAUUCCCAUGAGCAACGUAUAAGAAGAGUUCUAAUUGUUCCAUAUCCUCGUGAGCACUUGGUAUUGUCAGUUUAUUUUUUAAAUUGUUGGCAUAGACGUUUAGUGAUAUCCCACUGUGGUUUUAAUUUGCAUUUUCCUAGUGACCAGAGAUGUUGAACAUCUUUUCAUGUACUUAUUUAACAUCUGUAUAUCUUUCUUGGUGUUGUAUCUUUCGAAUUAUUGCUCUCUCUCUCUCUUUCUCUGUGUGUGUGUGUUAAGAGACAUGGUCUAACUCUGUCACCCAGGCUGGAGUGCAGUGGUGCAAUCAUAACUCACUGCAGCCUCAAACUCCUGGGCUCAAACAGUCUUCCUGUCCUAGCCUCUCAAGUAGCUAGGCCUAUAGGUGUGUGCCACCGUACCUGGCUAAUUUUUAUUUAUUUUUUAUUUUUAUGUAGAGACGGGGUCUCACUAUGUGCCCAGGCUGGUCUCAAACUGCUGGCCUCAACCGAUCCUCCUUUCUUGACCUCUCAAAGUGCUGAGAUUACAAGUGUGAGCCACCAUACUUGGCCUUCAUUGCUUAUUUAGCAGAGGGGUUUUGUGGUAUAAGUGAGUUCGCUUCUCAUCUUUUCCCACCACUGGCUCGGGAAUGAAUUAUGCUUUUGAUAUCAUAGCUAGGAACACUGCCUAGUUCAAGGUCACAAAUAUUUUCUCCUAUGUUUUAUUCUAAAAUUUUCUAGUUUUACAUUUUACACUUAGGUCUAUUAUCCAUUUUGCCAAUCUUUAUAUAAGGUUUGAGGUACAGGUUGAGUUGGUUUUUUGUGUGUGUGUAUGAAUAUCCAUUUAUUUCAGUGCAAUUUAUUGACAAAGACUAUGUUUUCCAUUGAAUUGCCUUUGUAUCUUUCUCAAAUAUCAACCAUAUAUGUGUGGAUCUAUUUCAGAACUUUCUGUUUGGUUUCAUCCAUUUGUUUGUCUGUCUUAAUACUAGUACUGUAUGGUCUUAAUUAUUGUGGCUUUAUAGUAUAUAUUGAAAUCAGGUUAUGUGAGUCCUUUAACUUUUUGCUUCCUUUUCGAAGUUAUUUUGACUAUUAUAGUUCUUUUGCCUUCCCCUAUACAUUUUAGAAUCAGCUUGUUAAUAUCUACAAAAAAUUUUGCUGCGAUUUUGAUUUGGCUUGCAUUGAAAUGCAUGGAUCCAUUAGGGAAGAAUUAAUUGUCAAAUUAAUACUGAGUCUUCCAAUCUAUGAAUGUGAUGUAGUUCUCCAUUUAUUUAAGCCUUCUUUGAGUUUUUUUUUCUCCCCAUCAGUGUCUCUGUACUGGUGUUAUUUUUCUUGGUUUAUUCCCUUGAUUUGGUAGACCACCUCCUUCAGUAGCUUACUGAGAAAGGCUCCAUGAGGGAAGUUUGUUGACACCUGGCAUGUUUUUAUUUUUAUGUCACAUAUGUAAUAGUUGAGUGGAUACAGAAUUCUAGGUUGGAAAUUAUUUUUCCUCAGAAUUUUAAAUGAGUUGUUCCAUUGCCUUCUGACUUCUAGGGUCGCUGUUGAAGUCUGCUAUUCUGAUUCUUGAUUCUUCAUAUUAAACUUAUUCUCUCUCAAACCUUUUAGGAUCUUCCUUAUAACCCAAGUUCUGACAUUUUUCAGCGAUGGGCCUUCUAUCCAUUAUGCUGGAUACAGUAUGGGCUCUUUCAAUCUGGAAAUUUCUGGUUUGCAAUUGGGAAAAUUUUUUCUUAAUUCUUUCUUGGAUUUUUUUCCCCCCAUUUCUUCCCCGUUUCUGAAUUUUCUUACCAUUUAAAAGUAUUUUUGAACUCCUUGUCUUUUCUCCACAAUGCAAUAGAUUUCCUUAAUUUACCUUUCAGUAUUUCUAUUGUGUUUUUAUUUCUGCUAUGAUUUCUAAUUUCCUAGUGGGUGCUUUUGUUCUUUUCAGUAUUCUUUUUUGUUUUUACAUCAUCUGUUAUCUCUCUGUGUGUGUUUUAAUUUCACUUCUCUCUGCAACUGCAUCAUCUUUUUCUUCCAAGUUAUUUUUUCCUGUUUGUCAUGGUAAAAGAUUCCUUAACUGUCUGGUCAUCCUUAGCUAUCUAGUUAUUAUUAAUAUUUAGGAACGGGGCCCUAAAAGAUUGUUUGAAAGCAUUGUAUUAUUUGGGUAUGGGAUUGUUGGCUGUGGCAUUUUCUGUAGAGUGGUCUGGCUCGCCUUUUUCUUCGGGAAACACUAAGUGUCAGUAUCGUUUGGUCAUUUCUCUUGGACUCAUCAGAUUUCCCCAAACAAGUCUCUUCUGGGCUCCUGGAAAGGAUAUUAAUCUGGCUGCCAGAGUCCUGGGACUCAAGCAGGGAAAGAAGGUUGGGGUGGGUGUUGGUUUCAAUAUUCAGUGUAUAAACUUCCACUUCAUCCUUUUGUUUUCUGUGUGGUACCUGUGUGUGGUCCAACUCUUCUGGGUAGAAGAGGGGCAGUUGUCCAACUGCACAGAAGAUCUGAAUGCUCUCAUGCAACCCAAUGAAUCCUUCAUUUUUAGCCCCAUUGUCAUCUCCAGUUCCAGAGAUAUAUUAAACCAUGAAUUCCUGAGUUUUGAGGGAGUUUUGUGGUGUAAGUGGGUUCACUUCCUAUCUUUUCCCACCACUGGCUCGGGAUUCAGCUUUUUCGAGUGUACUAGGUCAAUUUAUUCUCCCACCUGCUUCGUAGUUCCAAAUGUUUUAAAUCCCUCUAUUAUUUCAGUGGAGUUUUGGAAGGGAGCCGAAUUCAGUGCAUGUAUUCAGUUAGUCAACAUUUACUCUAAGUAGACUAUCCAAAUCUCUUUCAUUGAUCUGAGUUCUAUUUUAACGAUCUUCUUUUUUUUUUGAGACGGAGUUUCGCUCUUGUUGCCCAGGCUGGAAUGCAGUGGCGCGAUCUCUGCUCACUGCAACCUCCACCUCCUGGGUUCAAGCAAUUCUGCCUCAGCCUCCCGAGCAGCUGGGAUUACAGGCAAGCACCACCACGCCCAGCUAAUUUUUUGUAUUUAGUAGAGACAAGGUUUCACCAAGUUAAUCAGGCUGGUCUCGAACUCCAACCUCAGGUGAUCCGCCCGCCUUGGCCUCCAAAGUGCUGGGAUUACAGGCGGGUGCCACCGUACCUGGCCAACAAUUUUCUUAAAGUGGGGUAUGCAAAAAGCAACUCACUAAAGUAGAUAUAGGUAGUCCUUUCUUCUGGAUUCUUAAUGUUGCCUUAUGUUGAAUUCGCUUUUUCAACAACUUCACUUACGUUACCUUGCCGUUCACCAAAAGCUCUUAAGAAAGCCAGCUUUCCCUUUUGUGCUCUUGUUUCUUGUAGAAUUUUAAAAACAUAAGUAUGAAGUUGGAAUUUUCCCCAAGAAAUUUAAAGCUGUUGAUUUUUGCCCAGCUUUAUAGACUGUCAUGAGCUUUUAUUUUUAUUAUCCAGUGUAUGUGCUCUUCCUUUCCCAGGUUUCUAUUAUCUGAUUAAUAUUAAUAAAUUUAUGUCUGCAUAUUAAUUUAGGGAACACCUCCUAAUUGUGGCAUUCACUAUAGGGUGGCCUGGCUGGCCUGUUUGCUUGAGAAACCCCUAAUGGCAAUAUCUUUUGGCCUUGAUAUUAUUUAUCAUUUUGUUUUUAUUUUUAAACAUUUCCUUUCAGAUCCUCUCUUUAGACACUCUUUUUAACUGGUCACCUCUUUUCUCAAGACCAUUCUGGCAGUUUCCUAUACAGCUGACCUGUACUUUAGUCCAUUUCCUCCCAUGUUAUCCCCUGAAAUAUUACUAGAGUUAGGAUUAAUAAAUUUUAAUAAAAUUCAGGUAUAUCAUGUAUUUCCCAAUCUCCAUUCUUCUAUCAAAAAAGGACAAGACUUUAGCCAGGAAUGGCUUACUCAGGUGCAUGUGUUGGCUCUUACUGGUCCCCUCUUUCUUGUGUAAGUGCCCACAAACCCUCCCUUUGAUAUUUUGUUGUACAGUUUUACUGAGAGUUGACAUUAUGCUCAAUUGCUAAGUGGGUAGCAUUCACUUUCUUCCCCCUUUUAAAACCAGGGAUGCUGCCAUGUUCCUCUCUGUGUUGUAUUGCUGUGGUUUUCUACAGUUGCUUGAAGGUUACUGACAGCUGCCAGCAGUCUUCUUUGCACAAAUCCUCUUGGUGUUUGUUCAGGCGUGUGACUUGUCUGGACCACCAGGGUGUGAACUCUAACUUGGGAGACAGGAGAGGCAGGUCUUAAACUCUCUCGUCUUAGUGUGCCACACUGGUAACAUGUAGAAGACACUCAGUAAAUGUUUCAGUAAGCUUGUUUAUUUGAAACAGUUUACUCACCUACUAGAGCUUCAAUGUUUAUAGACCAAUAUUGAAUCCCAUCCCACUAAAUUUUGGUUAUACAUGUAAGGUGCUUUCUUGUGUUAAAGUGUUAAAAUUUAUUGAAAAAAAUAUCUUUUCCCAGUACCUGCUAAUGUCCCAAGCGUCGUGCUGGGCUUUGGAGAGAUCACAACACAUGACAGCUCUUACUGUCAUGGAACUCAGUGAUGUUUCGUGCAUGAUCAUCCUCUCCACUUGUUUAUUGACAUUGGAGGUGGCAUAUGUGAUGUCCCUUUUUCUAAAAAAUUUUCUCCUAAGACUGUCUGUAGUCUUUCUUUACGUAAUCAUAUCUGACAUGGGUCAACUUUGUUGCUGCCACCCUAGCCCAACUCAUGGUCGUCUUGUGCUUAGCUGCCUACAGUUCUUUCUCCACUCAAUAGCCUGAGUGAUCAAAAAGGUGAUUCAGACUCCACAUCCUCUCCCCUCCAGAGGCUUCCAUCACACUUAAAUAUAAUAUCCAGACUUCUUCUCUACCUUACUCUGGCUCUGCCUCCCUCUUCACCUCCCCACUACCAUCCUUCUCAUUUAUUAUGUUCUGGCCAAGUUCAUUGUUGUCAAACACCUCGAGAUCCUUCGUCUUUCAGGGCCUUCCUUUUCUCUCUGGCUCUACCCUUAGAUUUGCCAGACUUCCUCCCUCAGUUCUACACCUUGUACCCUAGCUGUCAUUUUCUGUUUCUUUACUUGGCUGUAUUUUUUUAAAAGCUGAUCAUCACCUGAAAUCAUUAUCUAUUUUUUGUAUUGGCUUUCUCCCACCAUAAGCACUGGGAUUUUGUCAGGUCUGUUGACUGCUGUAUCCCCAGUGUUAGAACAGUGCCUGGUCAAUGUUUGUUGAAUGAAUGAUGCAGUAAUUGUAUCAACUUACAUUGUUUCUUUCUACCUCUCUAUUUUUAGUUCAGAGCCCUUUGGAUGAGACAGGCGUUUCUGAACAAAGGCAUUCUUCCAGACUUAAUUAGGUUCCCUCUUCUAGGGUUAAGUGCUUAAUCUUUGCAGCAUCUUAAAACGGUAAAAACUAAAUUCUAUUCUUUGAUGCCAUCUAUGUAAUCAGUGGUUAACUUUCACACGCUUCUUUCCUGUUGGAAUAAUAGAUGAAAAGACCAAGCGUGGCUUUAAGUCCUUCUGUUUUAUAAUUCCUGGACACAUUUCUCAAAUUUCUGCUGCAGGUUUUCUUGUUAUCCCAUAAUCUUGACAGGUUUUCUCUCACCUCUUGGAUUCCUGCUGUCAGACCUUGUUAGGCUUGUUAAUUUUCUGUAUAGCAUGGAAUGAUGGUUUUCUAGAAGGUUCUGACAAACCCUUACUCUCAUUUAUCUUAUUGCUCCUCUGGUACAGAAUCUUUCAUUCCUCUCCUAUGUUCCCUUGUAUCUUUUUUUCCCCCUAAAUUACCUCCCUUAAUUCCAAGUGGGUGGAAGGAAAAGGAAUGGAAUUUGGUCUUAAAGGAUGAAUAAUGACUUCGUUGGAAUAUCAGUAAAGGAACUCUAGUCUGCGGGAAUGGUACGAGCAAACACAUAGAAGUGUGAAAUGUGUAAUGUGUUUGGCAAAAGUGGUUUGGGAUGGCUGGAGUGUGUGUUUAUCUCUAGUGUGAAGUCUGGCCAGAAAGGUAGAUUGUGAUCUUUUUCUUUUUUUUCUUUCAGACAGAGUCUCACUCUGUCACCCAGGCUGGAGUGCAGUGGUGCAAUCUCAGCACACGGCAACCUCCACCUCCCAGGUUCAAGUGAUUCUCCUGCCUCAGCCUCCCAGGUAGCUGGGAUUAUAGACACCUGCCAUCACGCCUGGCUAAUUUUUGUAGUUUUAGUAGAGACGGGGUUUCGCUAUGUUGGCCAGGCUGGUCUCAAACUCCUGACCUCAGGUGAUCCUCCUGCCUCGACCUCCCAAAGUGCUGGGAUUACAGGCGUGAGCCACUGCGCCUGGCCUGAUUGUGAUCUUAAAUGCUAGUUCUAGGGUUAUGGAAGUCUGUACUUUGGUCUCAUAAUAUUUUUGUUUCUCUGGUGUAGAAAUUAUUUUGUUAUGUUUUACAUACUAGUUGAAAGCAAGAGUCUGUUUUUAUUUUUUCCUCAUCUUCAACAGUAUCUAAUAGAGUAGCUUGCACAUAAUAAGAGUUCAAAGUUGAGUUGAAUUGAAUUCUGAUAAAAUGGUUUAAUUUUCCCAAGAAAAUCUAGAAGCCUGGACUCUUUCUACUGAAUUAAUCAAAAGGAGAAAAUACAUAACUUUUUUAAUUGUACACCUUAUAUGAGUCUGUACUGUAGAUAUUCAUUUUUUUGUCUUCUUUAUAUCUCCUACCUCACUUUUCCUUUUUGUAAUAUGUAAUCACCACAACAGGCAGUCUUGGGAUCAAGGAGAGGGGCUUGGGAGAUAUUUAACUCCUCAGUAUCUCCAUCAAGUCCCCAUUCUUUGAUAGGACAGUUAAUCUUUUCAUAAUCUUCAAUGCAGUGCUAUGCAGAGGCAUGUUCUUGUACCUCCUUCCAAUCAGAGAACUGCGUGUGUCCCUCAAUGCAGAAAAUCUGGAACCACCAUCAAGAACAAACUUAUAUACCUUUGAGAAAGGCUGAGAGAAAAAAAAAAAAGCCGUAUGUAUUAGGUAUCACUAUUCUCUUUACAGGUGAAAAAGCUGAUUCAUAAAGGUUAAAGGUCUAAGAUUAUUUAGCUAGUAAGCAAAUGAGUUGGAAUUAGAACACAGGUCUUAUAUUAUUUUCUUUCCUCUAUUUUUUAGGUAUCCCAAAUUCCACUUAAGGUUGAUGAAUGGCCUACUGGUCAGUUGAAAAAAUUCAAUUUGUGUAGCAUUGUCUAGCACAAAUGCUGAAAGUAGGUCUCCUCAUCUGCUAAGGGAUAUAAGCAAAUUCAAAGCCUCUGGCCUUUCUUGUGACACAUGCAUGAAAGUAGGUAAUAAAAAGAAAAGUAAAUAUUAUUUUAUGCCACAGUAAGUAUAAUGUUAAAAUAAUUUCAGUACGUUUAAUUUUCUUUCAUAUAUAUAUAUAUAUGUAUGUAUAUAUAAUUUUUUUUUUCUUCCUUGAGAUGAAGUCUUGCUCUGUCACCCAGGCUGGAAUGUAGUGGCGCGAUCUUGGCUCACUGCAACCUCCGCCUCCCAGGUUCAAGCAAUUCUCCUGCCUCAGCCUCCCUAGUAGCUGGGAUUACAGGUGCCCACCAGUACACCUGGCUAAUUUUUGUGUUUUUAGUAGAGACAGGGUUUUGUCAUGUUGGCCAGGCUCAUCUCGAACUCCCGACCUCGGGUGAUCCACCUGCUUCGGCCUCCCAAAGUGCUAGGAUUACAGGCAUGGGCCACUGCGCCCAGCCCGAUAAUUUUUAUUACAGUAAGUUUGAUUAGAGUAUGAGUGACCAAAAUCUAUUUCUAAAACAUAGAGUUAUUGGUGAAUUAGAAGGGGGUGGAUGUUAUUCCUUAUUGUCAACAUGGUUCAUGUAGACUGUGGAGAUGAAUGGAUUACAUUUGGCUUUUAUUAAUGCUUACAAGCUGUAUUUUUCCUUUUUUGCUUUUUUCUAGUUCUUAUUGAACAGGAUUGAUUUGAAAAAUUCACAUGUAAACUCAGGAUGCUGGGCUCUUAUAUCAUUUCAUGGUGGAUGAUUUGUGUAAAAUUGCAACUGAGUGAAUUUCAUUCAAGCAGUAGGAAUCUUGAAGAUAGCUCCAAACGAGAAUGGAAGCCGCUGGAGGACCGUAGCUGCACAGACAUACCAUGGCUGCUGCUCUUCAUCCUCUUCUGCAUUGGGAUGGGAUUUAUUUGUGGCUUUUCAAUAGCAACAGGUGCAGCAGCAAGACUAGUGUCAGGAUACGACAGCUAUGGAAAUAUCUGUGGGCAGAAAAAUACAAAGUUGGAAGCAAUACCAAACAGUGGCAUGGACCACACCCAGCGGAAGUAUGUAUUCUUUUUGGAUCCAUGCAACCUGGACUUGAUAAACCGGAAGAUUAAGUCUGUAGCACUGUGUGUAGCAGCGUGUCCAAGGCAAGAACUGAAAACUCUGAGUGAUGUUCAGAAGUUUGCAGAGAUAAAUGGUUCAGCCCUAUGUAGCUACAACCUAAAGCCUUCUGAAUACACUACAUCUCCAAAAUCUUCUGUUCUCUGCCCCAAACUACCAGUUCCAGCGAGUGCACCUAUUCCAUUCUUCCAUCGCUGUGCUCCUGUGAACAUUUCCUGCUAUGCCAAGUUUGCAGAGGCCCUGAUCACCUUUGUCAGUGACAAUAGUGUCUUACACAGGCUGAUUAGUGGAGUAAUGACCAGCAAAGAAAUUAUAUUGGGACUUUGCUUGUUAUCACUAGUUCUAUCCAUGAUUUUGAUGGUGAUAAUCAGGUAUAUAUCAAGAGUACUUGUGUGGAUCUUAACGAUUCUGGUCAUACUCGGUUCACUUGGAGGCACAGGUGUACUAUGGUGGCUGUAUGCAAAGCAAAGAAGGUCUCCCAAAGAAACUGUUACUCCUGAGCAGCUUCAGAUAGCUGAAGACAAUCUUCGGGCCCUCCUCAUUUAUGCCAUUUCAGCUACAGUGUUCACAGUGAUCUUAUUCCUGAUAAUGUUGGUUAUGCGCAAACGUGUUGCUCUUACCAUCGCCUUGUUCCACGUAGCUGGCAAGGUCUUCAUUCACUUGCCACUGCUAGUCUUCCAACCCUUCUGGACUUUCUUUGCUCUUGUCUUGUUUUGGGUGUACUGGAUCAUGACACUUCUUUUUCUUGGCACUACCGGCAGUCCUGUUCAGAAUGAGCAAGGCUUUGUGGAGUUCAAAAUUUCUGGGCCUCUGCAGUACAUGUGGUGGUACCAUGUGGUGGGCCUGAUUUGGAUCAGUGAAUUUAUUCUAGCAUGUCAGCAGAUGACAGUGGCAGGAGCUGUGGUAACAUACUAUUUUACUAGGGAUAAAAGGAAUUUGCCAUUUACACCUAUUUUGGCAUCAGUAAAUCGCCUUAUUCGUUACCACCUAGGUACGGUGGCAAAAGGAUCUUUCAUUAUCACAUUAGUCAAAAUUCCGCGAAUGAUCCUUAUGUAUAUUCACAGUCAGCUCAAAGGAAAGGAAAAUGCUUGUGCACGAUGUGUGCUGAAAUCUUGCAUUUGUUGCCUUUGGUGUCUUGAAAAGUGCCUAAAUUAUUUAAAUCAGAAUGCAUACACAGCCACAGCUAUCAACAGCACCAACUUCUGCACCUCAGCAAAGGAUGCCUUUGUCAUUCUGGUGGAGAAUGCUUUGCGAGUGGCUACCAUCAACACAGUAGGAGAUUUUAUGUUAUUCCUUGGCAAGGUGCUGAUAGUCUGCAGCACAGGUUUAGCUGGGAUUAUGCUGCUCAACUACCAGCAGGACUACACAGUAUGGGUGCUGCCUCUGAUCAUCGUCUGCCUCUUUGCUUUCCUAGUCGCUCAUUGCUUCCUGUCUAUUUAUGAAAUGGUAGUGGAUGUAUUAUUCUUGUGUUUUGCCAUUGAUACAAAAUACAAUGAUGGGAGCCCUGGCAGAGAAUUCUAUAUGGAUAAAGUGCUGAUGGAGUUUGUGGAAAACAGUAGGAAAGCAAUGAAAGAAGCUGGUAAGGGAGGCGUCGCUGAUUCCAGAGAGCUAAAGCCGAUGGCUUCGGGAGCAAGUUCUGCUUGAACCUAGCCGACGGUUAUGGAAACCCAUUGACAUUCCAAAACAAUAUAUACACAUAACUAUGUAUUUGUGUGUGUGGGUGUGUGUAUAUAUGUAUAUGUAUGUGUGUAUAUAUGUAUAUGUAUAUACACACACACACAUAAAUCAGCCAAAAUCAGAGAAAAGGAACAGGGAUUUAAUACCUUUUUUAUGCUUAUUUUUGUCAAACAUGUACUCCUUUCAUACGGGUGGCUUUUACAAGGCAACUUCCGUCAUUUAAUGUUUUCAACUGUAAUUGUCUUAAUGGAAAUGUUAAAAUUCAUAUCUGAUUAACAUUUUUAAUAACUUAGAGGAGAUUUUAACUUUAUUUAAAAAUAGGUAAAAUUAUUGUACCUAAUUAUGUCUAAAGUUUAUUCAGGGGUAAUUUCCCUGAUGUCUGUAUAAAAUCAAGAUCUUAUUUUACUGAUGCAUAAGUCCUAGUGGGUCAAGACUAGGCAUAUGCUUUCAGAUAAAUAAGGAAUUACUCCAAUCAGUUUUCCCCAAUCAAAGAAGCCAUGUCAUUUUACUUUUAGAAACAUACAAUUGGGCCCAAUAUGGGAAUUUUCAUAAUAGUUCAUACAUUUGUCAGCCAACAUUAAAAGGUAACCAACUCCUCAGGUAUUUGUAGUUUACCCUAACGCUUCUUUAAAAGAAAGUAGGUAAAAAAAGAAAAGGGUAGAUAAUCUUUCGUAUGCAAACUUUUCCCUUAUAUUUUGUCUUUCUUUCCUUUUUGACUUUAGUAGCAUCCUCCACACAUUUGUGUGCCUGAUUUGAAAGGAAGCUGGGGCACCCAGCGAGUUUAGCCUUUAAGUUUCUGUGUAUUGAUUUGCAGAUUAAGUAAUGCUGGGAGGAAUAAAGAAGGGACAGAAACAUGGAACAUAAAGCAUUGAAAAUUCCGGUGCUUGGGCUUCGGCUUCAGAGUAACGUCAGUGGCUUAGGGUUAAACGGCCAUUUUAUUCAAAUGCUUGCUAUACAAUCUGAAAACACACUGGCAGGUGCUCCUCUCCUUGGCAAUUCAUUGAGUAUCCAGAGUUCUACGAUGUUUAACUGAAGAAUUGGCUAAUGUUUUGAUCCUCCAGUGUGACUGUUGUUUUUGUUUGGGGGUGGGUUUGGGGUUUUUUGCUUUUUUAUUCCUGAAGCUUACCAGAUAUGAAUGGCUAAUACUCCAUUGUUCUGCUUGUUGUAAUGGUGAAUGCUUUAAGAAAAAAAAGUGUAAUUUGCUAAGAAUAAUUCAUGAUCUGUUUAUGCGAUAACUCCUUUUUGUUACAAUUUUUUUAAAAAAAGCUAUUUUUGUUAAUGUAAAGUAAAUAUUUCAGAGCAAAUUUUUUAAACUUAUUGCACUAAAUACAGGCUCUGUACAAAAAAAAAAAAAAAAAAAAAGCCUCAGCAUUUUAUCAUUCCAUGGAAGGAGAAUCUUUUGAAAGAAAGCAUUGCCUCCUACCAGAACUAGACAGUGAAUUAGAUCGGUAUUAUGGAAAUGCAUACAAGUAAUGUCACUAGGGCUUAAUAAGCAGCCGUUUGCUAAUGUGCUUCCUUUCAAAGGGUUGGACCUUUAAAUUGCUGCAAAAGGUAAAUUGUAUUUUUUUUUAAGUAUUGGUGUUCUUUACUCUAGCUAGGCUAAAAUUUGCUAAAUGCCUUGGUUUCUUUUAAAAGUUCAUGUAAUAUUUCUGAUUUUUCAGAAUAUUUGCAAUAAGAGUCUGGAUUUUAAAAAACACAUGCAUACACACAAUUAAGAGCUCAUGUCUUAGCAAGAUCUGGGAAACCAACAUUGCGAGAGUAGCUAUUUUGAAAGAAUAAUUCUCCAGAAGUUAACAUCUAAUAUCUAGUAUCACCAAACAGUAUCGCUGUUCUCUUUUAUUCAUUUGAAAUGAAUAUAAUUAUAUAACUAACAAUUGUCCAAAUAGAUGAGAGAGCAAAUCAUGUGAGAAAAUUCAGAAUACCAUCUGUUUCAUAGCCGCACAGAUUUUGGACUUUCACAAACAUUGGGAACUAAAUUUAGAAUUGGCAAAAGUCUAGAAGAUGGGUAUCAAAACAGAAGACAUUCCAGGAGCUAGCAAUUUUAAGAGGUGUCCCUCCAAAGUGACCUGAUGGAAGUCCUGAACUUGGAAAUUAGGUUCUACUCACUUGGACAUCCCUGCAUCAUGGACUGUUGCUGCUCCCUGUUCCAUAUGCUCGCAAUCUCAGCUAUUUGGAAGCUACCAGGAAUGCUUUCUAAUUAUCAUUUGCAACUAGAACUGUAAUCAGAAAGAAAUUUUGUAUUUUUGUAUAACUUGAUUGUGUGCCAUUUUAUAUAACAGGUCCUGUUUUACAAAUAAAUUUUGUUUUACUAACAUUGUGUUUAGAAAUUAUAAUCUAUGUGUAACCAUGUCAUUUGAGUUGCAAAUUAAUUGCCAGGCUGUUUUCCUUAAGUAAAUUCAUGUGCCGUGUAGAAAUAUGCAGAUAUGCAUUACACAGGCACACACAGAGAGAUAUUUAAUAUGUGGAAUAUCACUCUUUCAUGAGCUUUAUUCCUUGAUUAAUUUGAUAAAGCCUCACAGAGGAUUUUAAGCAAUAUUUAAAUGUGUUGAGGUUAUGUUUGGAUAUUCCUGCUGCCUCUUUUCAUUCAUUUCAAGUCAUUCUUCAGCUAGCUAUGGGCUGCCUUAUUGCUAUUCGCUCACUGCUUCCAUCUUCUGCCCAAGUGAGAAGAAUAGAUGAAGAACAGAAAUUUCUCUGUGAAAUGUGGAUACCCGAAUAAUUUCAUAAAUCAUUGAUUCUAUGUGGUGGUUUUUGUCUUCUUCUGUGGUGAAUCUUCAAAACUGUAUUCAGGACUCAUAUUUCUAGAGUUUUAAUUGGGGUCCUCUAUUGUCAAUUGUAGUAGUGACCAGAGUAUCGUGGUUUUUGCCAUCAGAUAAUUAAGGCUCUGGUGCAUAAUUUAGACUUUCUAAGCUCCUGCCUGAAGAAUAAGGUCUUCCAUAAUAUGGAAGAGAAAAGUUAUAUUUCAGUGUAAAUCCAAGAGACCCAUCUUCUAUGAGAGGCUUACCAGUGCAUUAGUAAUAAAACAUUAGCAAUUUAGCUAGAGCACUGAGAUUGUAUAAUCCUUGCAUGGAUGAGCAGAGCUCAAAGCCAGUUGUUCCUUUAAAGCAUUUAAUGCAAUGGCUAAUGUUUAGGAUUAAAGUUUUUAUUUUAUCCUAUAAGAUAAUUAAGUCCUAAGUCACUACAACUUAAGUAGCUUAACUGUAUGUUGGUACCCAAACUUUUUCUAUAAUGGUUAAGGAGGAGGCACUUACUGAGUUUAUUUUAAAGUUAUGCUAGAAAUGUUUUUCUUUUGUAGAGAUGCUCUCUCUCUCUCUCUCUUUUUUUUUUUUUUUUUUUUUUUUUUUCCGUGAGGGCAUUAGGCUGCUGAUUGUAAGUUAUUUCCAAUACCACUGAUCUUGGUAUCUGCCAAGGGCUUCCUUGCCUUCCCUGGGCAGUUUUAGGAUUUCACCCUAGUAGGGGGUAUGAGGCACUGACCCCUUUAUUCUGGACCCAAACUGCUUUAGAGCAGAGUUAAUACCUCUCCCUCCCUCUUCAAAACAGCUACAGGAACUGCAGGCACCACAUAUGUGUGAGGCCACAUCACUGCCCCUGAGGCUUCAACUAUUUCCACCAUGCACUAUUACUAGCUACUAACAGCCAUUUUAAGAGAUCUCCUAGCCUGCAAGGUAGAAUUCUGGGAUCAGUUCCAAAACCAGAACUGCCAGUAAUGGUGACUUGAAUAUUUUAUUUGAUUUUUGGUCAGUAACCUUGUCAUUUAAAUUGGACUUUCCAAUAGCCUUAACAUGGCCUCUGAGAAGUUUCCUCCAGAAAGGUCUUUAAGCUUUCGCUUUUCAAUAAGUAAGUUCUUUACUGCUUUUCUACUGCUACUUUAAAAAAAAAACAACAACAACAAAUAAAACUCUCAGAGUCUGGAGGCUUAUCAGUGCACCUGCCACAGUUAAUUUCUGUAUUCUUUUCAUACAUUCCAUCUGACACAUACGAGUGCACUAUAAUGGCUUGCCUAGAACUGGUAAGAAGUGGUCUGUGAAUGUAUAUUGAAAAAAUGUGGGUUCAUAAGUAAAAGCGUAACGCAGAUAUUUGUGUAUUCUGUAUUCACAGCGUAGGCUGCCUUUUGCUUUAAAUGCAUAUUCAUGUAUCUUUGUGUGCUAAGAAUGCAUGUUAGCCCUUUUGAAAAGUAGGCACUAUUCAUACACAGUAGCUUCUUGGAAUUAACUCAUCUUUGUUAACUUAGUGGCACAUAGUCCAAAUUUUUAAAAAGCAAGACCCUUGAAUAUGCCAAGAGAAAAUCUAAAGCUAGCAAACUUAAAAAACAAAACAAAAAUUACACGUCGUGUACAGUUAUGAAUUUAGAAUAGCACACUUUUUCCAUUCAGAUUUCAUACAUUUGAGCCAAAUUCUUAUACUCCAUGUUUUAAUUUUAAAAGGAUAAUUUUAAUCCAAGAUUUAAAUCUUUGAAAAUAUCUUUCUUAUAGAAAACUUUAAUGCAGUUUUUAAACUUACUGAUUUCUGUGGAAAACCUUUCUUUUCUAUAGAAAUACUGUAGUGCCCUUUCUUCCCAUCUUGAUUUUGUACAUGUAAAGACAAAUGAUGAUUCAGUUUCAAUAUUGCAUGAACAAUUGCCACUUUGUAAAUUAUAUGGACAGAAUGUGUUCUAAGGAAAUUCGUUAGUAAAUUUGUGAAAAACAUGUGAGAUUGUUCGAGACCUAUUAGGCUAUUCUUCAGUUUUGAUGCUCAGUUUUACAACUUAAAUGAUUUUCUCCAGGACACGGAGCUCAGAAUAAUAAAGCUUUUAUUAAUGGUCUAGUGAAGAUCUAGUUGAACAUGGAAACAUUGUAAUUUACAAAUGUCUCAGAAAUUUCUCACUUUUAUUUGCUAAGACCUGAAUUUAAUAUUUGAUAUUCAAAAACAAGUUAUUUUGAAGAGACAAUGGGUCUCUUUGAGCUUAAGAAAGCUAUGGACUAUCUUUCCUUCAAAUGCACAUCACAUGUCUGUGAACACUCAAAAUGCUCAUAGAAUUUCAGGGCCCUCAGACGGCCAGCUUCCACCCCUGUACCCCCUCAGGGGCUAAUGAACCCAAGUCAAAAGGCUGCUCUAAAGUUGUUCUGAUAAUGUGUUUUGAAAUGAGGAAGUGAUUAGGCCUCCACUAGAGAUACUUUUGAGAUGAUGCUUACCACCUUCUGACCUGGAAUCAUUUUUAUAACUUAAAGACUUUAUGUAAUUUAGUAGCAGGUUAGGGAAUAGAAACCACACUAAUCUGAAGGAAUAACAAGAUGAUCAACACUGAAUCUUCAUGACAGUAAGAUUUUCUUUCCUUGGAGGUAUGAGGGUGUGUAUGUGUGUGUGUGUGUGUGUGUGUUUGUGUGUGUGUGUGUGUGUCCUGGCGGUUAUUUGGGGGCAAGGUACCAGAUUAUUUGCAGUGAGCCAAAAAAAAAAAAAUAUCCAAGAAGAAAUAAAUAGGGAAUCCUUGUAAUUAAUCCAUCUACCAAAACACUUGAUUCUUUUUAUUGUAGCUCAGCUAUGACAUUAUGACAUUAUGUGGCUUAGUGUUAUCAGUAUACUACUGUCUUAAAAUAUAUUUGUCAACAUGUCCAGUUCCAACAACAGUUGAAGAUGAUGAUAAAUUAGCAAACUCAAGGGUAGUCCAUAGUUGGCAAAAAAUAAAUUUGGUAGAAAGUUGGAGGAGCAGAUGCUGAAGGUAGAAAUGCAAAAGAUGUUUUUUCUUCCUGCAUAAAUCACGGAGGUGUGUUCUGUUUUAGUGUUUUCCAGUCACCCACUAGAGCAGCUUCAGAUUCCUCUGCCAAUAGAACUCCACCCCCAGUCCCUUACCUACUCUAUCUUCUUUAGGGAAGCAUGUGGAUUUCUUCACAUCUGCACCUUACUAUUAGGUAAGGGUGCUGCAUCUACAUGGAAGGCUCCCUGGGCCCUUGAAAAAGCAGGCAGAAACUCAUCAAGGGGUUUGAAGUUCUUGUGAAAUUUGAUCCCAGUGGCUCAUGACUUAUAGUCAGGCAUCAAACCAUUUCCUACUUUUUCAGGCUGAAGAAAGUGGAAAUAUAACUGGCUGGUGAAGAAAGGAGAAAAGUCAGCCCCCUACCCCACCCCACACUCCUAGAAAAGUUUGGGGGUUUUUUUUGUUUGUUUUUGGUGUUUUUUUGAGACGGAGUCUCGCUCUAUCGCCAGCUUAGAGUGCAGUGGCUCAAUCUUAGCUCACUGCAACCUCCACCUCCCAGGUUCAAGUGAUUCUCCUGCAUCAGCCUCCUGAGUAGCUGGGACCACAGGCAUGUGCCACCACACCCAGCUAAUUUUUGUAUUUUUAGUAGAGACGGGGUUUCACCACGUUGGCCAGGCCAAUCUCGAACUCCUGACCUCAGGUGAUCCACCCGCCUCAGCCUCCCAAAGUGCUGGGAUUACAGGCAUGAGCCACCGCGCCCGGCCUAGAAGAGUUUUAAUGAACCUUCCACAGUAGUAAAUGCAGAGACCACUGGUGGAAAUUCCCAUGUUGGAUAGAAAAGGGCGUAAGUCCAGUCUAAGUAUCUAAAUGUGAUAUGCCCUUUUGUCACAGAAGUGUAAGACUUAAAGGGAAUAUUCUGACCUUCGUGUAUGAAUCUGAUCCACCCAUCCUGUCAGCUAGGAUUAUAAUUUGAACUGUCGUUUCAGGAGCAUGUGUUAAAUCAUAUGAGUAAAAAAAAAGUAGACAUUGAAAAGAAGACUUGGGAAUAAUUGGGCAGAUAGAAUGGGUUCCAUGGAUCAUUCUAGUUGCCACUAGAAAAUGUGAGCUCCUUCUUCAUUUACCAUGUUGAUAAUCCGGUGGUGACUUUUUUUUUUUUUUUGUAAAUUGUAUUAGAUACCCCACAGGAAUGUGACAAUAAUAGGAUAGCUUUGGGGGCUGGUGAUUUGAAACAGGGACUAUUAAGUAGAUUUUCCCCCAUCCUCUAGGUUCCUGUAGUCUGUGCUCAGAACUUGGUUUUUGGCCCCUAUUGUUUUUGCCUAUUUUGAUUUUCAGAGAUGAUCACAUGGGGACAGUUAACUUUUCUUCUGCUGUGUUGCCUUAAUGCUACUAGAUUGUGUUGUGUUGUUGGAGUUUUCUGACUUCUUCCCUAUAAAAAGAUACUGAGAGCUCCAUAAUGAAAGAAGUUGUUAUACUUUCUCAGAAUAUUCUGGACCACUGAAUGCACUUCUAAUAGAGCUUUAAUCUAAAGAAGUUAGUUCAGUGGUUAUUAACUGAUUUUAUUACAGGAGAAAAAAACUUUAACAAAAAGGCAGGGAGAAAAGUGUGAAGGGCAUCAAGCAAAAUGACAGGGGCUUCAAAAAACAACCAAAGACAAAACCCUAUCUUCUGAAGACCAAAGGUCCAACUUUACUUACUGGCUGGCACAGCCUUUCUGAACUCCUUGAGUUUAGAAUAGAGCUCCUAGAAUAAUAAGGCGGCCAAAUUUAAAGAUCAGUCAAUACAGUAGGGACCUGCUAUUGAUCUCUCAGGCACUGAGUCUUCACAUCCAGUGUCAAGCCCAGCCCAGCAUAUGGGGUGAUAUGAGCAGAAAACACACAUCGGUGUGUCUUGAUUUCUCGCAGCUGUGUAAUGUGGCAUGAGAAGUAUGUUUUGGUGCCACAUAUUUCUCAAUCUGAUGCCUUUUUGUCUUUUUUUUUUUUUGCCAUUUGCAUCCUAUUUCAUAGUGCCAAAAUGAAUUUUUGUAUCUUGUCUUGUCUUUGUCCAUUAUAAACUGGAGGAUCACAGUUAAGCCUUCCAUGAAUUCAUAGUUUGGAAUCAUUUACCUUACCAUUAUUUUGGAUUUUUUUCUUAUUACAGUGUCACUACACUGUAUUCAUGUGGGGGAACAAACAUGUAGGUGCUUGAACAUGCCCCACAGACACAGUUGUAGCCCUAGUAUUUGUGACGGUCAUUAUUGACACAGUGCAGACUUUGCAGAUGGAGCAUUAUGCUCUCAGAGGACUUUAAAAAUAUGUAUAUUAAGCAAUUAACUUUCUGGAGUUGGAGUUAUCAAAUCUUGCUGGGAAAUUAACUUCCAAGAGCUCUGAAUUGGAUGGAAUUCCAUCUGGCUUCAGAGAACAAUCAGCCUAUAUGAAACGGAGCUUUGAAAUGUUUUUCUUGUGCAGAAAUACGAACUAGAAAGAAAAGUGCUGAUCUAAUGCUAAGUUUUCUCUGUGUACUGACUCAGUUGCCAGAAUUAUAAUGAAAACUGUAUUUUAGUCUAACAAAUGUAUAGAAUUUUUUAUGUAAUAAAUAAAAUUUUAUAGGAAAGAA